ACACUGCACGCAGGCUGGGCCGACUGGGGAGCUCAUAGGCCAGGCUCUGACACCCAGGCAGGGCCUAGGGUGGGACGAUGGCAGGUGGGGGCAGCGACCUGAGCACCAGGCUGUUCACGGAAGACCAGGAUGUAGAUGAGGGACUUGUCUAUGACACUGUAUUCAAGCACUUCAAAAGACAUAAGCUGGAGAUAUCAAAUGCAAUAAAAAAGACAUUUCCAUUCCUUGAGGGCCUCCGCGAUCGGGAACUCAUCACAAAUAAAAUGUUUGAAGAUUCUGAAGAUUCUUGUAGAAACCUGGUCCCUGUACAAAGAGUGGUGUACAAUGUUCUCAGUGAACUGGAGAAGACAUUUAACCUGUCAGUUUUGGAAGCACUGUUCAGCGAGGUCAACAUGCAGGAAUACCCCGAUUUAAUUCACAUUUAUAAAAGCUUCAAAAAUGCAAUCCAAGACAAAUUGUCUUUCCAAGAAAGUGAUCGAAAAGAAAGGGAAGAGAGGCCUGACAUCAAACUAAGUCUUAAACAAGGAGAAGUGCCAGAAAGCCCGGAAGCAAGGAAGGAAAGUGACCAAGCAUGUGGCAAAAUGGAUACUGUGGAUAUUGCAAACAACUCUACUUUGGGAAAACCCAAGAGGAAAAGAAGAAAAAAGAAGGGGCAUGGCUGGAGCAGAAUGGGAACGAGAACGCAGAAAAACAACCAACAAAAUGAUAACAGCAAAGCCGAUGGCCAGCUGGUCUCGAGUGAAAAGAAGGCGAACAUGAAUCUGAAAGACCUUUCCAAGAUUAGGGGGAGAAAGAGAGGCAAACCUGGAACCCACUUUACUCAGAGUGACAGAGCUCCACAGAAAAGAGUCCGAUCAAGAGGUAAAAAAGAAAAGAGGAAUGCACUUUCAAUAACUAAACAUCUAAUUUCCUGUGCUUUAUGCUGUAUUUUCAGUAAUAAACCUAUUUCUUUAAUUGUUUUAUGAAGCUAUACUAACUAUUGAAAAACAUAUCUUAUUAAGUCAUUUUCCAAAAUGUAUCAAGGAAAGAAGGAAGUAAGUUGGUGAUGGAUCUACAACCAGACCCUGGGGCCCCAGGGGGUCACUAAAGUGCUACUUCCACUGAAAUGAUAAAUUUCAAGGCUGAAGAUAGGCCAUUGCUGUAUAAAGGGUAUAACCCGUAAGUGAUUUAGCUGAUCUUCCUCUGGCUACACAGAAAGCCACAUGUUGCACACUAAGGUUGAACCAGAGUUGUGGUUAGAGAUCUGUGUCCUAAGGCUUUUUGGCUUUUUAAAAAAUCUUUGACUGUGUGAUCUUGUGCUGACCACUUGGCCUUCUUUGCCUUGGUUUCCUCAUCUGAGAAGCUAGAGGAUGAAUUAGGCCAACCACCCUUCUUAUUAGUCCAUCCCAGUCUAAAUAGUGUGCCCUUUUCAAAACCAGUCUCAGGACCAAAGACCGCUUCCCCUGCCCAUCAUGGCCUCUACACCUCUGUUUGGAAGGGCAGGAUUAGCUGCUCAUCCUCCUGGAGUUUUUCUUUGAAAAACUUUCACACCUACUUCUGUAGUAUCCGGUUCUCAGUUCCCCACCCCCUGCUAGGUACAAUUUUCAGAUUAUUCUAGAGCUCCCUGAGCUCCUUUCUCAGCUGUGGAGAAAGCUGAUAGGAGGGGAAAAUGGAGCAAAGCAGAGAAUAAAAGUAGAAGGCAGGUGCUGUCUCCAUUAGGUUAUCUCAUCAUUAGCCUCUCCCUCCUUGACCAGUCAGUGCCCAAAUGGGAGACUGAUUAUGGUCUCUGGCUUCAUCUCUGGCUACCUAACUGCAGCAAAACAGAAUAGCUGGAGAGCGCCCAUCAAACCAAUGACAACAACUGUAUGUUUCAUUGUCAUAUAAGAAUCAGUGGAGCUUACUACACUGGAAGUUAAAACAGUUUUACUGAAGUCUAAUUUCUCUGAUAAAGCAUUCAAUUUUCUGUGAAAUUUGAAAGGUGAAAUUGGGGCACACAUUCUGUAGUUACCGAUCAAAAAUGCCACUUGGAAGAAAGACUUUGAAACUCUAGAGAUUUAUGGAAUAGAAUUUCCUAAGUACUCUUUGUGCCUUUAUAGGAUUUACCUCAGUGGGAAGGGGGGAUGUGCCUUUGCAAAGUGAGACAGAAUGAAGAAAUCCUCUCUUUCAGCUUCAAGAAAGCACAAAGAUGAAACUGUGGAUUUUCAGGCUCCUUUACUUCCAGUGACCUGUGGUGGGGUGAAGGGAAUUUUACAUAAGGAGAAAUUGGAACAAGGUGGGUUUCAUAGUCUUCUUUAAUUUGCAGCUCCUAUCUGAAGGCAUCACAAGAAGUGGUGAAAUUAUUUGUGUGAAUUACACAUCAUUCAAGGAGUUUUGGGCCCAGUUUAGCUUGAGGGAAGGAGGAAGGGAUCCCUAAGAUGACAUUUUAAGACUUUAAGAAAUCACACCCAUUAGACGCUGACUCGCACAUGGAGUGUCCAGGGGGUACCCAAAGAACAAAAGAGAAGGCAGGAACGUCAAUUCACAGAUGGAAAAUGUCAGGUAUUUUACUUUGAAUCAGACAGAAAAGGGAAGAGGCCCUCAACCUCAAGCUUCAUAUUCUCUCUCCCUUCUGGAGUGCUGUCACCAAGGCAGGGUGCUUGGCUUGGGUGAUGAUCACAGGUUUUAACAUUAGGAAGCCUGAGUUCCAGCCUUGGCUGUGCCAGGAAUGACUGUUCCAUUCUGAGUAGAGAAGGGGACCUUUCUGAAUGUGAAAUCUCUCAUCCAAGAGAGGGAACAAUAAUUAAAAACCUACCUCAUGAUGUAGCUGUGAGAAUUAAUUUACAUAUUAAUGUAAAAUAUUUUACGAUUGAAAAUUAUAAAACUGUCAAAAAUGUCUAUCAGAAUGGCCUUCAUCUCAGACCUCUCUUAACUUGGCUCUUUGAGCACCAAUUAAUAUAAACAUUUUCAUUGUGACUUUUUUUAACAGCUUAACUGAAAUACAGUUCAUGUAUCAUGUAACUCACCACUUAGAGUAUACCAAUCAAUGAUUUUUUUUGUAUUUUCACAGGAUUGUACAGCCAUUAUUAUCACCUAAUUUUAGAACAAUUUGUCCUUCACUAAAGAAAACCCCAUGUCAAUUAGUAGUCAAUGCCCAUUCCCACCUCACCCCAAUGCCCAGCCCUAAGCAGCUGCUAAUCUAUUUUCUGCUCUAUAAAUUUGCUUAUUCUAGGCAUUUUCUGCAAAUGGAAUCCUAUCAUACAUCCCCUUUCAUGACUGGCUGCUUUUAAUCAGCAUGAUGUUUUCAAAGUUCAUUCAUAUUGUAUUAGUACUUCAUUUCUUUUCUUGAUAAAUCAUAUAUUUCAUUGUAUAGAUAUACCACAUUUUGUUUAUCCAUUCAUCAACUUGGGUUAUUUUCACUCUUUGGCUGUUAUAAAUAAUGCUGUUUUGAACAUUUAUGUAACAAAUUUGGUGUGAACAUAUUUCAGCUCUUUGGAGUGUAUAUUCAAGAAAGGAAUUGCUGAGUCAAAUGGUAAUUCUAUUCUUAACUUAUUGAGGAAACACCAAAGUGUUUUCCACAGUAGCUGCACUAUUCUAUAUUCCCACCAGAAAUGUAUGAAGGCUCCCAUUUCUCUACACACUCACCAACACUUGUUAUUGUUUGUCUUUUUUAUUAUGAUCAUCCUAGUGAGUGUGAUGUGGUAUCUCAUUGUGGUUUUGCUUUGCAUUUCCCUAAUGGCUGAUGGGGUUGACUAUCUUUUAUAUAUAACUUAAUUUUUCUAUUAGGUAACAUUUCACAAUUAUUUUUUAAUAUCAGCUGCCCAUGAUUGCACAGAUGAGAAAAUCUCUGUUCAAUAAUGCCCUAAAACUGAAUGAAAAAUGUUGUAAUAGAAGGUGCAUAUGUUGCCAGUGUGGCCUCCUGAGCCACAGGGCACCUAUCUCAGACUGUACCCCUAAGUAAGGAUUCUGCCUCCACAUUGCCUCCAGAGCCAUCUGCAGACUCAGGCCUGGUCUCUACUCCCAGAAUUCAACAGCAAGUUGGAGUCCUCUCAUCUUUCAGAAUCACUUGCUUUUCCUUCUGUA